GGCUCUGGCUCAGCGGCGGCUCCGGUGGCAGCGGCGGUGGCGGCUAGGCGGGCUCGGCGGCUCCUGUCCCUCGGGCGGCUGCCCGCUCGCUGCCCAGGGCGCCCGGACACACGUGGGCGGCUCAGCGAUGGCCCGCGCCCCGCGACGUGGCGGGCAGGCACCGGGGCGCGGGACCGCUGAGCCCGAGUGAGCCGGGGCCGCGCUCCCGCCUUCGGCCCGGGCCUCCCGGGAUGGCCGUGGCGCCUCUGCGGGGGGCGCUGCUGCUGUGGCAGCUGCUGGCGGCGGGCGGCGCGGCACUGGAGAUCGGCCGCUUCGACCCGGAGCGCGGGCGCGGGGCUGCGCCGUGCCAGGCGGUGGAGAUCCCCAUGUGCCGCGGCAUCGGCUACAACCUGACCCGCAUGCCCAACCUGCUGGGCCACACGUCGCAGGGCGAGGCGGCUGCCGAGCUAGCGGAGUUCGCGCCGCUGGUGCAGUACGGCUGCCACAGCCACCUGCGCUUCUUCCUGUGCUCGCUCUACGCGCCCAUGUGCACCGACCAGGUCUCGACGCCCAUUCCCGCCUGCCGGCCCAUGUGCGAGCAGGCGCGCCUGCGCUGCGCGCCCAUCAUGGAGCAGUUCAACUUCGGCUGGCCGGACUCGCUCGACUGCGCCCGGCUGCCCACGCGCAACGACCCGCACGCGCUGUGCAUGGAGGCGCCCGAGAACGCCACGGCCGGCCCCGCGGAGCCCCACAAGGGCCUGGGCAUGCUGCCCGUGGCGCCGCGGCCCGCGCGCCCUCCCGGAGACCUGGGCCCGGGCGCGGGCGGCAGUGGCACCUGCGAGAACCCCGAGAAGUUCCAGUACGUGGAGAAGAGCCGCUCGUGCGCACCGCGCUGCGGGCCCGGCGUCGAGGUGUUCUGGUCCCGGCGCGACAAGGACUUCGCGCUGGUCUGGAUGGCCGUGUGGUCGGCGCUGUGCUUCUUCUCCACCGCCUUCACUGUGCUCACCUUCUUGCUGGAGCCCCACCGCUUCCAGUACCCCGAGCGCCCCAUCAUCUUCCUCUCCAUGUGCUACAACGUCUACUCGCUGGCCUUCCUGAUCCGUGCGGUGGCCGGAGCGCAGAGCGUGGCCUGUGACCAGGAGGCGGGCGCGCUCUACGUGAUCCAGGAGGGCCUGGAGAACACGGGCUGCACGCUGGUCUUCCUACUGCUCUACUACUUCGGCAUGGCCAGCUCGCUCUGGUGGGUGGUCCUGACGCUCACCUGGUUCCUGGCUGCCGGGAAGAAAUGGGGCCACGAGGCCAUCGAGGCCCACGGCAGCUAUUUCCACAUGGCUGCCUGGGGCCUGCCCGCGCUCAAGACCAUCGUCAUCCUGACCCUGCGCAAGGUGGCGGGUGAUGAGCUGACUGGGCUUUGCUACGUGGCCAGCACGGAUGCAGCAGCGCUCACGGGCUUCGUGCUGGUGCCCCUCUCUGGCUACCUGGUGCUGGGCAGUAGUUUCCUCCUGACCGGCUUCGUGGCCCUCUUCCACAUCCGCAAGAUCAUGAAGACGGGCGGCACCAACACAGAGAAGCUGGAGAAGCUCAUGGUCAAGAUCGGGGUCUUCUCCAUCCUCUACACGGUGCCCGCCACCUGCGUCAUCGUUUGCUAUGUCUACGAACGCCUCAACAUGGACUUCUGGCGCCUUCGGGCCACAGAGCAGCCAUGCGCAGCGGCCGCGGGGCCCGGAGGCCGGAGGGACUGCUCGCUGCCAGGGGGCUCGGUGCCCACCGUGGCGGUCUUCAUGCUCAAAAUUUUCAUGUCACUGGUGGUGGGGAUCACCAGCGGCGUCUGGGUGUGGAGCUCCAAGACUUUCCAGACCUGGCAGAGCCUGUGCUACCGCAAGAUAGCAGCUGGCCGGGCCCGGGCCAAGGCCUGCCGCGCCCCCGGGAGCUACGGACGUGGCACGCACUGCCACUAUAAGGCUCCCACCGUGGUCUUGCACAUGACUAAGACGGACCCCUCUUUGGAGAACCCCACACACCUCUAGCCACACAGGCCUGGCGCGGGGUGGCUGCUGCCCCCUCCUUGCCCUCCACGCCCUGCCCCCUGCAUCCCCUAGAGACAGCUGACUAGCAGCUGCCCAGCUGUCAAGGUCAGGCAAGUGAGCACCGGGGACUGAGGAUCAGGGCGGGACCCCGUGAGGCUCAUUAGGGGAGAUGGGGGUCUCCCCUAAUGCGGGGGCUGGACCAGGCUGAGUCCCCACAGGGUCCUAGUGGAGGAUGUGGAGGGGCGGGGCAGAGGGGUCCAGCCGGAGUUUAUUUAAUGAUGUAAUUUAUUGUUGCGUUCCUCUGGAAGCUGUGACUGGAAUAAACCCCCGCGUGGCA